AGAGGGUCCUGCUGGCGCGAGGGUGGGUAGGAGGGGACGCGGGGACUCGGCCCCCAACACCGCGCUCCGUCUGCAGCCGCCGCCUCUGCACCGCCGCUGCCCGGCGGUCGGUUCAAAAAACAGAAAUCGGGUUUGCUGCCCGGCGGACAGGCGUGAAGAGCAAGGGAAAGGAACUUCCUCCACCUUCGGGGCUGGAGCCCUUUUCCUCUGCAUCUCCAGUCUCUGAGUGAAGAUGGGGGGCCUGACAGCCUCGGACGUACACCCGACCCUGGGGGUCCAGCUCUUCUCAGCUGGAAUAGCGGCGUGCUUGGCGGACGUGAUCACCUUCCCGCUGGACACGGCCAAAGUCCGGCUCCAGGUCCAAGGUGAAUGCCCGACGUCCAGUGUUAUUAGGUAUAAAGGUGUCCUGGGAACAAUCACCGCUGUGGUAAAAACAGAAGGGCGGAUGAAACUCUACAGCGGGCUGCCUGCGGGGCUUCAGCGGCAAAUCAGCUCCGCCUCUCUCAGGAUCGGCCUCUACGACACGGUCCAGGAGUUCCUCACCGCAGGGAAAGAAACAGCACCUAGUUUAGGAAGCAAGAUUUUAGCUGGUCUAACGACUGGAGGAGUGGCAGUAUUCAUUGGGCAACCCACAGAGGUCGUGAAAGUCAGACUUCAAGCACAGAGCCAUCUCCACGGAAUCAAACCUCGCUACACGGGGACUUAUAAUGCGUACAGAAUAAUAGCAACAACCGAAGGCUUGACGGGUCUUUGGAAAGGGACUACUCCCAAUCUGAUGAGAAGUGUCAUCAUCAAUUGUACAGAGCUAGUAACAUAUGAUCUAAUGAAGGAGGCCUUUGUGAAAAACAACAUAUUAGCAGAUGACGUCCCCUGCCACUUGGUGUCGGCUCUUAUCGCUGGAUUUUGCGCAACAGCUAUGUCCUCCCCGGUGGAUGUAGUAAAAACCAGAUUUAUUAAUUCUCCACCAGGACAGUACAAAAGUGUGCCCAACUGUGCAAUGAAAGUGUUCACUAACGAAGGACCAACGGCUUUCUUCAAGGGCAAAAUACCCCACAUUGGGAAGUGAAGAGAAACAUGUUAAGAGACUUGAAGGAAAAAAAUUGGGGCAGAGGGGUGUUUUUUAUAGGUUAAACAAUAAAAGCCAUUUAAACAGUAACAAUUUCUCUAAGGACAAGAAUCGUCAAGAUUGAGACAGCACUGAUUUCUUGACUCUACUCAAUACUUCUUUGGUUUCUCUUCUUCCUUCCCCCUUCUAAUAGUUUCCUACCUCCCAUUCAGAAAGCAAAGCAAAACAAGCAAAAAUUCCCCCUUCCCUCAAAAAAGGAAAGAGUUUUUGAAAAAGUUCAUGUCAGUGAAGAAAAGACAUGUUUUGGGAGUGAAGGAUAUUUGUGGAUUUGUAUAGAUGUGAUCAUCAGGGCUGUGUUGUUUUGAAGUAAUAUAGGACAUCUAGAGGAAAAUUUAUUUUCAGCAGAGGAGGGAAAGAUGAAGAGUAGGUACUUUUAAGCAUCUUCACUUGAGGAGUGGCAAAAUGAGAAGCAUAACCUGCUAUAAUCACUUUAAGAAUUUCAGGCUGAGUGUGGUGGUGCAGUCUCUAGUCCCAGUUACUCCAGGAGGCUCAGGUGGGAGGAUCACUUAAGCCCAGGAGCUCGAGGUUGCAGUGAGCUAUGAUUACACUACUGCAUUCCAGCCUGGGCGGCAGGGUGAAGCCUCAUCUC